GAAAAUAGAUCAUCAUGGUGGCACCAAAGAGUCACACAGAUGACUGGGCUCCUGGGCCUUUCUCCAGUAAGCCACAGAGGAGUCAGCUGCAAAUAUUCUCUUCUGUUCUACAGACCUCUCUCCUCUUCCUGCUCAUGGGACUAAGAGCCUCUGGAAAGGACUCAGCCCCAACAGUGGUGUCAGGGAUCCUAGGGGGUUCCGUGACUCUCCCCCUAAACAUCUCAGUAGACACAGAGAUUGAGAACGUCAUCUGGAUUGGUCCCAAAAAUGCUCUUGCUUUCGCACGUCCCAAAGAAAAUGUAACCAUUAUGGUCAAAAGCUACCUGGGCCGACUAGACAUCACCAAGUGGAGUUACUCCCUGUGCAUCAGCAAUCUGACUCUGAAUGAUGCAGGAUCCUACAAAGCCCAGAUAAACCAAAGGAAUUUUGAAGUCACCACUGAGGAGGAAUUCACCCUGUUCGUCUAUGAGCAGCUGCAGGAGCCCCAAGUCACCAUGAAGUCUGUGAAGGUGUCUGAGAACUUCUCCUGUAACAUCACUCUAAUGUGCUCCGUGAAGGGGGCAGAGAAAAGUGUUCUGUACAGCUGGACCCCAAGGGAACCCCAUGCUUCUGAGUCCAAUGGAGGCUCCAUUCUUACCGUCUCCCGAACACCAUGUGACCCAGACCUGCCAUACAUCUGCACAGCCCAGAACCCCGUCAGCCAGAGAAGCUCCCUCCCUGUCCAUGUUGGGCAGUUCUGUACAGAUCCAGGAGCCUCCAGAGGAGGAACAACGGGGGAGACUGUGGUAGGGGUCCUGGGAGAGCCAGUCACCCUGCCACUUGCACUCCCAGCCUGCCGGGACACAGAGAAGGUUGUCUGGUUGUUUAACACAUCCAUCAUUAGCAAAGAGAGGGAAGAAGCAGCAACGGCAGAUCCACUCAUUAAAUCCAGGGAUCCUUACAAGAACAGGGUGUGGGUCUCCAGCCAGGACUGCUCCCUGAAGAUCAGCCAGCUGAAGAUAGAGGACGCCGGCCCCUACCAUGCCUACGUGUGCUCAGAGGCCUCCAGCGUCACCAGCAUGACACAUGUCACCCUGCUCAUCUACCGCAGGCUGAGGAAGCCCAAAAUCACGUGGAGCCUCAGGCACAGUGAGGAUGGCAUCUGCAGGAUCAGCCUGACCUGCUCCGUGGAGGACGGGGGAAACACUGUCAUGUACACAUGGACCCCGCUGCAGAAGGAAGCUGUUGUGUCCCAAGGGGAAUCACACCUCAAUGUCUCAUGGAGAAGCAGUGAAAAUCACCCCAACCUCACAUGCACAGCCAGCAACCCUGUCAGCAGGAGUUCCCACCAGUUUCUUUCUGAGAACAUCUGUUCAGGACCUGAGAGAAACACAAAGCUUUGGAUUGGGUUGUUCCUGAUGGUUUGCCUUCUGUGCGUUGGGAUCUUCAGCUGGUGCAUUUGGAAGCGAAAAGGACGGUGUUCAGUCCCAGCCUUCUGUUCCAGCCAAGCUGAGGCCCCAGCGGAUACACCAGAACCCACAGCUGGCCACACGCUAUACUCUGUGCUCUCCCAAGGAUAUGAGAAGCUGGACACUCCCCUCAGGCCUGCCAGGCAACAGCCUACACCCACCUCAGACAGCAGCUCUGACAGCAACCUCACAACUGAGGAGGAUGAGGACAGGCCUGAGGUGCACAAGCCCAUCAGUGGAAGAUAUGAGGUAUUUGACCAGGUCACUCAGGAGGGCGCUGGACAUGACCCAGCCCCUGAGGGCCAAGCAGACUAUGAUCCCGUCACUCCAUAUGUCACGGAAGUUGAGUCUGUGGUUGGAGAGAACACCAUGUAUGCACAAGUGUUCAACUUACAGGGAAAGACCCCAGUUUCUCAGAAGGAAGAGAGCUCAGCCACAAUCUACUGCUCCAUACGGAAACCUCAGGUGGUGAGAACUACAUUCUCUGUAUCCCAAGGCCCACAGAGUGAGGAACUAUUCCUUAGACCCUUUGAACUGAAAAUCCGAGAUUCCCAUGGCUAAGGAUCUUAAAUUCUACCCACUAUGCACCCCUCAGAUACAUUCCAUGGUCAACAGAGAUGCAUAAACAAAUAUUCCUGACAUCUGUGUGACCAAAGGCUGAACAUUUCUAAUUGAUUUAAUAAUAUCUUAUGUUGGUUAUUUUUAACACUGACCUGAAUGACAGCUUAUACACUCAAACAAGGUAGGGUCUUUAUAGCUUUUUAAAUCUAUCUCUAACCCUAAUCCUAAUCUACCUAAAUGACAACUUCUCAAAACCAUUGAAAAUUAGCUAACAAUUUAACAACAAGAAUUUUUGGAAAAUACACCACCACCUACAGUACAUUAGUUUUAUUCUAGUGUUUAAAAAAAUCCCAGCCGGGCGCGGUGGCUCAUACCUGUAAUCCCAGCACUUUGGGAGGCCAAGGCGGGUGGAUCACAAGGUCAGGAGAUGGAGACCAUCCUGGCUAACAUGGUGAAACUCCGUCUCUACUAAAAAUACAAAAAAAAUUAGCCAGGCGUGGUGGCAGGCGCCUGUAGUUCCAACUACUCAGAGACUGAGGCAGGAGAAUGGCGUGAACCCAGGAGGCAGAGCUUACAGUGAGCCAAGUUCGUGCCACUGCACUCCAGCCUGGGCAACAGAACAAGACUCCAUCUCAAAAAAAAAAAAAAAAAAAAAAUUCCCAGCCUGGGCAACAUGGUGAAACCCUGUCUUUAUAAAAAGUUCAAAAAAAAUUACCCAGGCCUGUGGUGGUACACACCUGUAGUCCCAGCUACUUAGGACACUUAAGUGGGAGGACCGCUUGAGCCGGGGAGUUCAAGGCUGCAGUGAGCCAAGAUCAUGCCACUGAAAUCUAGCCUGGGUGACAGAGUGAGACCAUGUCUUAAAAAAAAAAAAAAAUCCCUUACAGGUAGAAUUUAUCAUUAAAUAAUCAUAAUGAUAAUAAUAACUGACUUGCUUUUAUAUGAAGUUUUGCAGUUACAAUACCUUGAUACACAUUCUUCUUUGAUCUUUGUAAUACUUCUAGAAAAGUGUUGUCAUCCACAUUUUAUAGCCAAAGAAACAGAUUCAAGGAAGUUAAUUUUGCCUAAGGUGACAAAGAUAGUACUUGGAAGUUCCAGUAUUAAGAACCAUGAGGCGUUUUAAGAUCAUCCUGAGUAAUCUUAAAUAAUUCACCUUGAUCUGGCUGUCCAUUUCAUUUUCACUUUCCUGAAAACAUCGUGUCCAUUCAUACUUUUGCUUUCAAAUCUCCCCCAAAUUCCCUCCCUAUAACAUAUUCAAAAAAAUAUUUUUUAAAAAACUCUCGGCUGGGCGUGGUGGCUCAUGCCUGUAAUCCCAGCACUUUGGGAGGCCGAGGCAGGUGGAUCACCUGAGGUCAGGAGUUCAAGACCAGCCUGGCCAACAUGGUAAAACCCCAUCUCUACUAAAAAUAUUAAAAUUACCUGAAUGUGGUGGCAGGCACCUGUAAUCCCAGCUACUCAGGAGGCUGAGGCAGGAGAAUUGCUUGAACCCAGGAGGUGGAGGUUGCGGUGAGCAGAGAUCACACCAUUGCACUCCAGCCUGGGCAACAAGAGCAAAACUCCAUCUCAAAAAAAAAGAAAAGACUACAGUUGACCCUUGAACAAUUCAGGGGUUUAGGAGUGCCAACCCCACCCCACUCCAUGCAAUCAAAAAUCAUUCUAUAACUUUGACUCUCCAGAACUUAACUACUAACAGCCUACUGUUGACCAGAAGCCUUACCAAAAACAUAAACAUUUGAUUAACACAUAUUUUGCAUGUUACGUGUAUUAUAUACUGUAUUCUUACAAUAAAGUAAGCUAGAGAAAAGAAAUUAUUAAGAAAAUCAUAAGGAAGAUAAAAUAUGUAUACUAUUCAUUAAGUGGAAUUGGAUCAUUGUAAAGGUCUUCAUCCUCACCUUCACAUUGAGUAGGCUGAGGAGGAAGAGGAAGGGUUGGUCUUGUUCUUUCAAGAGUGGUAGAGGUAAAAGAGGUAGAGGAGGUAAAAGGGGAGGCAGGAGAGGCAGGCACACUCAGUGUGAUGUUUAUUGAAAAAAAAUCUGCAUAUAAGUGGCCAUGCAGUUCAAACAUAUGUUGCACUUAUGCCUGGUGUUCCAUUAUUGGAACACUAAGCGUGUAGGAGUUAUUUAUAUUCUACUGCUCAAGAUCAUCACCAGGGUCUGAUUUUUCACUCAUGCACAAAUUCAAAAAAUUGCAACCUCCUGCGUAAAUGGGUUAAAGUUACUUGACUACUUAAUAAAUUGUAUGCACAGUUCCUAAGGGUUUUUCAGAAGCUGAAGGUGGGGGAUAUCACUGCACUGUGGUAAAGAGGAAACACAUCAUGAAAAAGGAAUUUGGGUUGGGCCUUAAAAGAUGGAUAGAAUUUGCUCAGUAAACACUUGUUGGGAUGUGUGGUUUGGUUCAACCAUCAUCCAUCUCAUCCUGACUUCUAGACAGUAGUCUAAUGCUUAGCCAGCUAGAGACUUUGCCUUGGAACCUAAGGCCAAAUCUGUGCUGUUCACUGCAUUCCCAGAGCUGCUUUCUACUCUGGCCUGGCCCUUUGUGUUUGGGUCAAUACCGGUCAAACUUAAAGUCAGUCCCUGCUCUGAGUUUCAGAAUGACCACCACAUGUCUGGUCAGUCCUGCAAGGCACACACACUACCCUGGAGACUGAGACCCCUGAAACCACCUCACUUACAGUGUAAGUUGAAAUCAUUGCAUUUCCUGAGCCAAACUCUUGACAACUAUAUCUUUUGUCUUCAGAAUUGUCAGGACCAGGAAUUCUGGUUUUGGAUCUCUGAAGGCCAUUAUUGCCUACUUGAUCUGGAAAUUCUCAAACCUACUUUAGUUCUUAUUUCUGAUAUACCUCUCUGUACAACAUCUCAAAGGUUUAUGCUAUCCCCAAGCUGUUGCUGGUACCCAACCUCCCGCUCCUCUGGGUCAGCACAGAGCUUAUCUGCUCUUUAGAGCCUUCCCUGAACACUCUCAGACAGGGAAGCCUAAGAACCCUUGGGAACAGCUUGGGGACUAAUGGUCUGGACCAUUACUUUGGAACUUAACCUCUGCCAUCUAAAUUAUCUUCUUAUAAAUGUUCGUUUUGUUUCUCCAGCUAGGGCAGAGAUUGGAAUCAUUUGACAGUAGCUUCGUGAGGGCAAGCCCCUUCAUUGUCAUUUUUUUAUCCCCUGGAUUUGCUGCACUAAACUGUCUUGUGUUGUCCUUGCAGAGAGUCCAGCCCACAGCCUUUCCUAUUAGGAGCCUCCAUAAAUGCUUGGCAUCAGGCUGGUUGAUUGCGCCAUCCCUGGGCCAGCACAUAUGACUCUACUUCUGUAGGAUGGACCAGUCAUAGCCUGGCCUUGCCUUCCUCUUUCAUCAGCCUCACUCUUCCAAGGCUUUAUUAACCAUAUUCUUUUGUGGAUUUUUGGCUCACAGGUGGUGCCACCACCACAACAGAAUGAUCUUGAGAUUCCUGAAAGUCCUACCUAUGAAAAUUUCACCUGAAAGGAAAAGCAGCUGCUGCCUCUCUCCUGGGACCGUGGGGUUGGAAAGUCAGCUGGACCUCAUGGGGCCUGGGGCUCACAGACAGAAGCACCUCAGAAUUUCCUUCAGUGCCUCAGAGAUGCCUGGAUGUGGCCCCUCCCCCUCCUUCUCACCCUUAAGGACUCCCAAACCCAUUAAUAGUUCAGACACAGGCUCCUUCUUGGAGCCUAUGGGCUUCAGAUGUCUUUGCCCCAUUUGUCACCUCGCACACUUAUAGCGUUUCCUCCUCGAAAUUCUACCAAGACUGGUCAAAUGUUGCUGAGGGGCCUGGACCAGCUGUCCUUUACACCACCUUCUCAACACUGCUGAAAAGAACCCAAGAGAAUUGUCACACAUGACACAAGAUGUACAUAAUAUCAUGCUCACUGCAGUGUUAUUUAAAAUAAAAGGCAGGAAAUAA